ACACUACGCCAGAACAAGAUGGCCGACGCGGCGGCCACAGCUGGGGCCGGUGGCUCCGGAACGAGAUCGGGAAGUAAACAGUCCACUAACCCUGCCGAUAACUAUCAUCUGGCCCGGAGGAGAACCCUGCAGGUGGUUGUGAGCUCCUUGCUGACAGAGGCAGGGUUUGAGAGUGCCGAGAAAGCAUCCGUGGAAACGCUGACAGAGAUGCUGCAGAGCUACAUUUCAGAAAUUGGGAGAAGUGCCAAGUCUUACUGUGAGCACACAGCCAGGACCCAGCCCACACUGUCCGAUAUCGUGGUCACACUUGUUGAGAUGGGUUUCAAUGUGGACACUCUCCCUGCUUAUGCAAAACGGUCUCAGAGGAUGGUCAUCACUGCUCCUCCGGUGACCAAUCAGCCAGUGACCCCCAAGGCCCUCACUGCAGGGCAGAACCGACCCCACCCGCCGCACAUCCCCAGCCAUUUUCCUGAGUUCCCUGAUCCCCACACCUACAUCAAAACUCCGACGUACCGUGAGCCCGUGUCAGACUACCAGGUCCUGCGGGAGAAGGCUGCAUCCCAGAGGCGCGAUGUGGAGCGGGCACUUACCCGUUUCAUGGCCAAGACAGGCGAGACUCAGAGUCUUUUCAAAGAUGACGUCAGCACAUUUCCAUUGAUUGCUGCCAGACCUUUCACCAUCCCCUACCUGACAGCUCUUCUUCCGUCUGAACUGGAGAUGCAACAAAUGGAAGAGACAGAUUCCUCGGAGCAGGAUGAACAGACAGACACAGAGAACCUUGCUCUUCAUAUCAGCAUGGAGGAUUCUGGAGCCGAGAAGGAGAACACCUCUGUCCUGCAGCAGAACCCCUCCUUGUCGGGUAGCCGGAAUGGGGAGGAGAACAUCAUCGAUAACCCUUAUCUGCGGCCGGUGAAGAAGCCCAAGAUCCGCAGGAAGAAGUCCCUCUCCUGAGCUGAGAAGGAAACCUGGCUUGUACAGGGGCGCAGAUUCCACCCUCCCGGGGAGUUAAAGCCACUCAAGGGAAGAAGAGGGUGACCUCCUCAUGGCCAAGCCGAGGCUGCAGGGUGUGAUCGGACAUGAUUUUCAUGGCAAACCGUCUUAUUAAGAUGACCUAUUUUCACUGGAUGUUUGGGUUGAGGAAGAUAUGAACAGAAUAAUGAGAAUUUUUUUUUUUAUUUUGAGAUGGAGUCUUACUCUAUCACCCAGGCUGGAAUGCAGUGGUGUGAUCUCAGCUCACUGCAGUCUCAGCAACCCUGGGUCCAAGUGAUUCUCCUGCCUUGGCCUCCCGAGUAGCUGGGACUAGAGGCAAGCGCCACCAUGCUGGCUAAUUUUUGUAUUUUGAGUAGAGAUAGGGUUUCGCCAUGUUGGCCAGGCUGGUCUUGAACUCCUGACCUCAAGUGAUCCACCCGCAUUGGCCUCCCAAAGAGUUGCGAUUACAGGUGUGAGCCACCACGCCCAGCUAAUUUUUGUAUUUUUAAUAGAGAUAAGGUUUCGCCAUGUUGGCCAGGCUGGUCUUGAACUCCUGACCUCAAGUGAUAACCCGCCUCGGCCUCCCAAAGUGCUGAGAUUACAGGCGUGAGCCACCGCACCCCACCAGAGACUUUCUUAAUCAAUCAGGCUAUGUGGUGGGGCAUAGCAGCAGCCAGUGACUUCGUUCAUUAUCACAGGAUUUGAUUCCUUUGAAACUCAAGAGACCAGGGAAAGUGACAGGAAGGAAAGGGCUCUUUGCUGCUGUGCUUAUUACAAGGAAGACUGUUUGUCCAGCGUGUAUUUCAGGAUAUCUGGAUCCCUUUUAUUGACUCACAAUUUGUGGCACCACUUUCUCAUCCCAGAACUUCAUUCUUAUUUCUCUCCUCAUCUGGCCUCCCAAGUGCUCCGUUGAGCUGAUGAAAAGUUCUUUGUACUCCCUCAACGUGUCGGAAACAGGAGGCCACACAGCACAGCUUUGUUUGGGGUGGGCAGGAGUCAGGAGUCUUGAGCAGAUGCAUCACUGUGAAGAAGAACGACAUGUCGGGGCUGCACCUGUCCUCCCGUCGGCAUUUGACGAAAGCUCCCUGAAGCGGGGCAGCACUCUCCUCCUGAGAGAUUUACCAUUUAUUGCCCCUGUGAGGAAUGUGUGCUUGGGAACUGCCAAGUCUUACCCCUUCUGGAAGAAGAGGUUUUCUCUGACAAGAGCCUAGAGCGUCGGCUCUAUUAUGCUGGGACUUGACAGAGGAGCCAUGGGGUUUAAACAGUAGGAAAGAGGGGCUACGCGCAGUGGCUCACGCCUGUAAUCCCAGCACUUCGGGAGGCGAAGGCAGGUGGAUCACUUGAGGUCAGGAGUUCGAGACCAGCCUGGCCAACAUAGUGAAACCCCGUCUCUACUAAAAAUACAAAAAUUAGCCGGGUGUGGUUACUCAUGCCUGUAAUCCCAGCUACUCGGGAGGCUGAGGCAGGAGAAUCACUUGAACCUGGGAGGCGGAGGUUGCAGUGAGCCGAGAUCGUGCCACUGCACUCCAGCCUGGGUGACAGAGCGAGACUCCAUUUCAAAAAAAUAAAAAAAGGAUAAAGUAAACAAUAGGAAAGGAUUUGGUGGGGUGAGGGUGGGGUGUUGAGGGCUGGGCCUCAUCUUGUAUUCUGAAAGCUGAGAAACGGCUGGUCAGCUGGAAGGCUGGUGGAUGGGCAGGAGUGAGCCAAGCUGAGGCGUUCUGCAAGAAGCAGGUCUGAGUCUGUCCAACCAAUUUGUAUCCUGUGGGGAGAACAACUUCAUUCUUAACAUACCCUACAAACCAGAAAACAAGUUUUUAAGGAAGAUGCUGGGCAUGCUGAUAGCUUUUCUGGUCUCCUAAGGAAGAGUUUUUAAAACUAAAUCCAAGGAAGAAAAAUGUAACAACACGUGGAAGUGAACACUGGAUGAAUAAGCUUGUUUCCCAAAUUAGAAUCCUAACGUCCAUAUUUAGCUUCAUGUAUUCCCCUUUGGCUUCCACAGUUCAACUCCUUUUAUUUUGAGACAGGGUCUCGCUGUGUCGCCCCAGCUGGAGUAUAGUGGCACUACCUCGGCUCACUGCAACCUCCACUCCCCGGGUUCAAGCAAUUCUCAGAGUAGCUGGGAUUACAGAUGCCCGCCACCACAUCUGGCUAAUUUUUUUUUUUUUUUUUUAGUAGACACGGGAUUUUGCUAUGUUGCCCAGGCUGGUCUUGAACUCCUGGCCUCAAGUGAUCCACCCGCCUUGGCCUUCCAAAGUGUUGAGAUUACAGGCGUGAGCCACGGUGCCCAGCCCAUCUCUUAGUCUUCCAUUCCCUUGGUGAAUUUGGAAACUUGAAAAACUUGGGGACUUGACAGCAGGCUCCAUGUUCUUCUGGCCUCACUGUACUGUGUAAGGAAAGAGCUGCUUGUCAGGAACGGAAGAGGGGACGCUAGUAAAAAAAAAAAAAUUGGAUUCCCCAACUGGACUAAAUAGGAGUUUUUCAGGUUUGUAGUAACGUGAAACUCUCCUAGAUCGAAGCAGUUAGACUGGCCUAUGUGGCCUUCUCAGGGUUUGUGAUUCAGUUCUUAGCGAUUCUUGGCCUGAUAAGUUUAUGAACACAGCCCCACAUUCAAGCCGUGGCCAAUCCCAGCUGUUCUCACUGCUCUUGGGAGGUGUUGUCCCAGUCAGUGUUUCUGCAGCUUCCAUUUGUUGUUGUUAUCCAGUGUAAGCACCUGUUGAAUGCAGAUGUGCUGAGUUAGAGGUGGGAUUUGGAAAAGGGCUGCUAUUUCUGCUGUUGAGAUUUCAGAGGCUAUACUCUUUUUUUUUCUUUUCUUUUUUUUUUUUUUUUGAGACGGCAUCUCACUCUUAUCGCCCAGGCUGGAGUGCAAUGGCGUGAUCUCGGCUCACUGCAACCUCCACCUCCUGGGUUCAAGGGAUUCUCCUGCCUCAGCCUCCUGAGUAGCUGGGAUUACAGGCACCUACCACAAUUCUCGGCUAAUUUUUUUUGUAUUUUUGGUAGAGACGGGGUUUCACCAGGUUGGCCAGGGUGGUCUCGAACACCUGACCUCAGAUGAUCCACCCACCUCGGCCUCCCAGUGUGGGUGGGAUUACAGGCAUGAGCCACCGCGCCUGGCCUCAGAGGCUAUACUCUUAUAAUUUUGUUCUGAGGGGAGACAGGGAAAGGGUUAGACAACUUGAAACAUUGACCCUGUAUAAAAAUGCAAAAUUCUCAAUGUGUAUUUAUAAAUUUCUAUUUUUUAUAACUUUAUGGGACUUCUUAGAGGCCAAAAGUAGUAAACAUGCAGAUUAAAAAUGUUUAUGAAAAUCUCAAUAAAAAUUCAUAAUAAAAACUUUGUAAAUAAAUAGAACUGUAAGCUUUGAACUUAAUUUGUGUUCAAAAGUUAACAGCAAUGUGGACAAAUAAGUCAGGCUUAGCCCUUGUGUUGGCCUAAGCACACCUGGGAACUUAGUAAAACUUUUAUUUUGGAAAUUUUCAAAUACAAAAUUAGAGAGCAAAAUAUAUGAACCCCUGUAUAUGCCUCAUCAAGCUUCCACACUUGUCAGUAGCUUGUUGAUUCUGUUUCAUCUGUUUCUCCCACUUUUUGUCCUUUAUUUUCUUUCCUCCUGGAGUGUGUGUGUGUGUGUGUGUGCGUGUGUGUGCGUGUGAGACAGAGUUUCGCGCUGGAGUGCAAUGGUGCAAUCUUGGCCCACUGCAACUUCUGCCUCCCGGGUUCAAAUGAUUCUACUGCCUCAGCUUCCUGAGUAGCUGGGAUUAUAGGUAUCUACCACCACCACCACGCCUGGCUAAUUUUUUCUUUUUUUUUUGGAGACGGAGUCUCGCUCUGUCGCCCAGGCUGGAUUGCAGUGGAUUGUCAAGAUUGCAGUGGUGCAAUCUCAGCUCACCGCAAGCUCCGCCACCCAGGUUCACGCCAUUCUCCUGCCUCAGCCUCCCAAGUAGCUGGGACUACAGGUGCCUGCUACCACGCCCAGCUAAUUUUUUGUAUUUUUCAGUAGAGAUGGAGUUUCACUGCAUUAGCCAGGAUGGUCUCGAUCUCCUGACCUCAUGAUCCGCCCGCCUCGGCCUCCCAAAGUGCUGGGAUUACAGGCAUGAGCCACCGCACCUGGCCUAAUUUUUUUGUAGGUUUAGUAGAGAUGGGGUUUCACCAUGUUGGCCAGACUGGUCUCCAACUCCUGACCUCAGGUGAUCACCUGCCUCAGCCUCCUAAAGUGCUGAGGUUACAGGCGUGAGCCCCCGCGCCUGGCUCUUCUGGAGUAUUUUUAAAUGCAAACUCCAGACCUGUGUCAUUUAAUCUAAAUGUGUCUAUACGUAUCUCUGAUUGAUCUUUCUUUAAAUUUUAAUUUUGGAAUAAUUAUAGAUUCACAAGAUGUUGCAAAAAAUGUUGAGAGAGAUCCUAUGUACCCAUCACCCACUUUCUCCCAGUGGUAGCAUCUUGCAUAACUGUGGUGCAAUAUCAAAACCCUUGCAUUCAGUUUCAGUGUACAAUGUAGAUGGUAUAUUAGUACAAUGCAUAGAGCUUAUUUAGUUUUCACCAUGUGCACGUGUGUGUUAUGUGUGUGUUGUUCCGUGCAGUUUCAUCGUGUAGAUUUGUGUAACCACCAGCACACAAAUGGUGAAGACACAGAACCAUUGCAUCAGUACAGUUCUCCCUCAUGCUGUCUCUUUGCAAUCACAUCCACCUCUCUGCUCUUCCACUUCUCUCCUGGCAGCCACUACUCUGUUCUCUAUCUCUAAUGUUAUUGAAAGAAUGUUAUAAAUUGAAUCAUAAAGUAUGUGACUUUUUUCUUUUUGAGACAGAGUCUUGCUCUAUCGCCUAGGCUGGAUGGAGUGCAGUGGAGCGAUCCCAGCUCACUGCAACUCCUCCACCUCCCGGGUUCAAGAGAUUCUCCUGCCUCAGCCUCCCAAGUAGCUGGGAUUACAGGCAUGUGCCACCACACCCAGCUAACUUUUGUAUUUUUAGUAGAGAUGGGGUUUCACCAUGUUGGCCAGGUUGGUCUCCAACUCCUGACCUCAAGUGAUCCGCCCACCUCAGCCUCCCAAAGUGCUAGGAUUAUAGGUAUGACCCACCGCACCUGGCCGAGUAUGGGACUUUUUGACGUUGGCUUUUUCAGUUCUGCAUAAUUCUCUUGAGGUCCAUCUAGGUGGUUGUGUGUAUCAGUAGUUCCUUUCUUUUUAUUGCUGAGUAGCAUGGAGGCACCAUAGUUUAACACAGUUUCUUUAACCAUUCACGCAUUGAGACAAAAAAAGUUCUUAAUUCUGCGAACAUCAACUUCCUGUGCCCAGGUGCAAGUGCGGGGGCAGCUGGCCCAGGGUAGAGCUUUACCAUGGACCCUGGCGCUCCUGGAAAAAAAUUCAAGGUAUUUUUCCUCCUCUUGGAGCGUGUGGCCUACCUCAUCUCCAUUUGAUUACUAGCUUUUCUUUUUCUCCUUUGUUAAACAGUUAUUUAAUUUUGAAGAGAUAAUAUAUGUAUACAGUAUAAAAUUUAAAAGACAGAAAAAGAUAUAAGUGAUAACAAAAUAUCUUCCUCCUCCCCUGUUUCCCAGAGGCUCAGACCUCAUCCCUGGCAGCUGCUAUUAUGUUACUGUCAAUAUGACCUUAUGUAUUCUUCCAGAAGUAUUCUGUGCAUCAAAUGCAAAUACUUAUAUUUUCUACUUCUCAGUGUAUUUUUUGGUGAUGUUCCAUGUCAGUAAUAAAGAGCUUCUCUGUUUCGUG